AGUCUCGGUUAGCUUCACUUCAGCGGGAACCUGCCCACUAAGGAGGCCGAUUCUUUCCGGCUCGAGCAGGUCCGGACCCGCCCCUCUGGCGUCUAGCAGUCUCGGAGGCCUGCCCGUAUAGUUCAGGGCCGGACAGCGAGCGGCGGCGACUUGCCAGUAAGGGUUUGGAGUCAUCAGCAGGUUUAAUUUUGGAGGAACUUUACAGGUUUGGCUCCAGCAGCUGCUGUUGCCACCACCACUAGUUCAAGCACCAUGCAGUUUACCUCAAUAUCAAAUUCUUUGACCUCCACUGCUGCUAUUGGGCUCUCAUUUACAACUUCAACGACUACCACCGCCACUUUCACCACCAACACUACUACCACAAUCACCAGUGGCUUUACUGUGAACCAAAACCAACUGUUAUCAAGAGGGUUUGAAAACCUUGUACCUUAUACUUCAACUGUUAGUGUAGUAGCAACUCCUGUGAUGACAUAUGGUCAUCUGGAGGGUCUUAUAAAUGAGUGGAACCUUGAGCUGGAAGAUCAAGAGAAGUACUUUCUUCUCCAGGCCACUCAGGUCAAUGCUUGGGACCAUACAUUGAUUGAGAAUGGUGAGAUGAUUCGUAUUUUACAUGGAGAAGUGAACAAAGUGAAACUGGAUCAGAAAAGAUUGGAACAAGAAUUGGAUUUUAUCCUGUCACAGCAGCAGGAACUAGAAUUUCUGUUGACUUAUUUAGAGGAGUCUACGCGUGACCAGAGUGGACUUCAUUAUCUGCAGGAUGCAGAUGAGGAGCAUGUGGAGAUCUCCACCAGAUCUGCAGAAUUCUGAAUGCCCAUAUGGACUCCCUGCAGUGGAUUGAUCGGAAUUCAGGCAUGCUGCGAAGGAAGGUAGAAGUGGUAACACGGGUUUUCGAGGAUUAUCGUCACGAGGAGCAUGCACACAAUGUCAACACUGCUUUUUAGUGAAUGACCAUAUCUUCAGCAUGUCGUUUCUGGAUUAUUACCUACAAAUUCUGAUGUUAAAUAGAGUAGUAUUUAUACUUAAUAUUUCAUCUUGAUCAUAAUGAAUUGUGCAUCCUUUUUUUCAUUUAAGUAUUGUACUGUUGAGAAUUAUACCUUAGUUUUGUUUUUAGUAUUAGAAAAUCAAAAUUAUACUAGCCCCUUUGUCCAGACAGCAACCUCUUAGAUGCUGACUCUAUAUGUGUAAUUUAUGUCUUACUCUCCCUGGCAUCAGUACACAUCAUCCUUCUCACUCCAGUUGAAUCAUAGGGUGAUGUCUGCCAAAAGUACAUGCCAACCUAUAUAGUGCUAGAUACUGUAAAGUCUCUUCUCCUCAAAGGAACCUACUGUCUAGUUUGAGAUAUAAUUAAUGCUUGUCUGCAUAAAAACAAUAUAGAUAAUAUAAAGAAGUGCAGUAUGAAUUAUAGAAAGUGUGUUAUAGAGAUUCAGAGCAGGGAGGAAAAGUUAGGGUAGAUUAUUAUUAAAGGGUUAAGGAAAGGUAAGUUUCAAGGAAUUUGGUUAUUUUUAAUGUAUGGAUAUACUGGCAUUUUAUUUGGUUUUAGCAUAUGAUUUAUAGUUGGUGAUUUCCGUAUAUUUGUUUGUUUUUCUUUUUUUUUGUUUGUUUGUUUUGUUUUGUUUUAAAUAAGCCUUGUUCUUAGGUUUGGAACAGUCUGGUCUCCUGUGUUUCAUGUUUCACCUAAGUCAUAAAUAAAGGUAAUGUCCUAAAAAAAAACAUGUAAUACUGAAAUUAACUAUUAAAAGUUUUUAAGUGACUAGA